AGUCUCAGCGUGGGGUGAAGCCUAGCAGCUAUGAGGAUCCAUUAUCUUCUGUUUGCUUUGCUCUUCCUGUUUUUGGUGCCUGUUCCAGGUCAUGGAGGAAUCAUAAACACAUUACAGAAAUAUUAUUGCAGAGUCAGAGGCGGCCGGUGUGCUGUGCUCAGCUGCCUUCCAAAGGAGGAACAGAUCGGCAAGUGCUCGACGCGUGGCCGAAAAUGCUGCCGAAGAAAGAAAUAAAAACCCUGAAACAUGACGAGAGUGUUGUAAAGUGUGGAAAUGCCUUCUUAAAGUUUAUAAAAGUAAAAUCAAAUUACAUUUUUUUUUCAAAAAAA